AGUGGUCCUGCCGCCUGGUCUCACCUCGCUAUGGUUCGUCUGCCUCUGCAGUGCGUCCUCUGGGGCUGCUUGCUGACCGCUGUCCAUCCAGAACCACCCACUGCAUGCAGAGAAAAACAGUACCUAAUAAACAGUCAGUGCUGUUCUUUGUGCCAGCCAGGACAGAAACUGGUGAGUGACUGCACAGAGUUCACUGAAACGGAAUGCCUUCCUUGCGGUGAAAGCGAAUUCCUAGACACCUGGAACAGAGAGACACACUGCCACCAGCACAAAUACUGCGACCCCAACCUAGGGCUUCGGGUCCAGCAGAAGGGCACCUCAGAAACAGACACCAUCUGCACCUGUGAAGAAGGCUGGCACUGUACGAGUGAGGCCUGUGAGAGCUGUGUCCUGCACCGCUCAUGCUCGCCCGGCUUUGGGGUCAAGCAGAUUGCUACAGGGGUUUCUGAUACCAUCUGCGAGCCCUGCCCAGUCGGCUUCUUCUCCAAUGUGUCAUCUGCUUUCGAAAAAUGUCACCCUUGGACAAGCUGUGAGACCAAAGACCUGGUUGUGCAACAGGCAGGCACAAACAAGACUGAUGUUGUCUGUGGUGAGUCCUGGACAAUGGGCCCUGGAGAAAGCCUAGGAAGGUCCCCAGGAUCGGCUGAGAGCCCUGGUGGUGAUCCCCAUCAUCUUCGGGAUCCUGUUUGCCAUCCUCUUGGUGCUGGUCUUUAUCAAAAAGGUGGCCAAGAAGCCAACCAAUAAGGCCCCCCACCCCAAGCAGGAACCCCAGGAGAUCAAUUUUCCCGACGAUCUUCCUGGCUCCAACACUGCUGCUCCAGUGCAGGAGACUUUACAUGGAUGCCAACCGGUCACCCAGGAGGAUGGCAAAGAGAGUCGCAUCUCAGUGCAGGAGAGACAGUGAGGCUGCACCCACCCAGGAGUGUGGCCACGUGGGCAAACAGGCAGUUGGCCAGAGAGCCUGGUGCUGCUGCUGCUGUGGCGUGAGGGUGAGGGGCUGGCACUGACUGGGCAUAGCUCCCCGCUUCUGCCUGCACCCCUGCAGUUUGAGACAGGAGACCUGGCACUGGAUGCAGAAACAGUUCACCUUGAAGAACCUCUCACUUCACCCUGGAGCCCAUCCAGUCUCCCAACUUGUAUUAAAGACAGAGGCAGAAGUUUGGUGGUGGUGGUGUUGGGGUAUGGUUUAGUAAUAUCCACCAGACCUUCCGAUCCAGCAGUUUGGUGCCCAGAGAGGCAUCAUGGUGGCUUCCCUGCGCCCAGGAAGCCAUAUACACAGAUGCCCAUUGCAGCAUUGUUUGUGAUAGUGAACAACUGGAAGCUGCUUAACUGUCCAUCAGCAGGAGACUGGCUAAAUAAAAUUAGAAUAUAUUUAUACAACAGAAUCUCAAAAACACUGUUGAGUAAGGAAAAAAAGGCAUGCUGCUGAAUGAUGGGUAUGGAACUUUUUAAAAAAGUACAUGCUUUUAUGUAUGUAUAUUGCCUAUGGAUAUAUGUAUAAAUACAAUAUGCAUCAUAUAUUGAUAUAACAAGGGUUCUGGAAGGGUACACAGAAAACCCACAGCUCGAAGAGUGGUGACGUCUGGGGUGGGGAAGAAGGGUCUGGGGGAGGGUUGGUUAAAGGGAGAUUUGGCUUUCCCAUAAUGCUUCAUCAUUUUUCCCAAAAGGAGAGUGAAUUCACAUAAUGCUUAUGUAAUUAAAAAAUCAUCAAACAUGUAAAAA